CCUGCAGAGGAUCAAGACAGCACGUGGACCUCGCACAGCCUCUCCCACAGGUACCAUGAAGGUCUCCGCGGCAGCCCUCGCUGUCAUCCUCAUUGCUACUGCCCUCUGCGCUCCUGCAUCUGCCUCCCCAUAUUCCUCGGACACCACACCCUGCUGCUUUGCCUACAUUGCCCGCCCACUGCCCCGUGCCCACAUCAAGGAGUAUUUCUACACCAGUGGCAAGUGCUCCAACCCAGCAGUCGUCCACAGGUCAAGGAUGCCAAAGAGAGAGGGACAGCAAGUCUGGCAGGAUUUCCUGUAUGACUCCCGGCUGAACAAGGGCAAGCUUUGUCACCCGAAAGAACCGCCAAGUGUGUGCCAACCCAGAGAAGAAAUGGGUUCGGGAGUACAUCAACUCUUUGGAGAUGAGCUAGGAUGGAGAGUCCUUGAACCUGAACUUACACAAAUUUGCCUGUUUCUGCUUGCUCUUGUCCUAGCUUGGGAGGCUUCCCCUCACUAUCCUACCCCACCCGCUCCUUGAAGGGCCCAGAUUCUACCACACAGCAGCAGUUACAAAAACCUUCCCCAGGCUGGACGUGGUGGCUCACGCCUGUAAUCCCAGCACUUUGGGAGGCCAAGGUGGGUGGAUCACUUGAGGUCAGGAGUUCGAGACCAGCCUGGCCAACAUGAUGAAACCCCAUCUCUACUAAAAAUACAAAAAAUUAGCCGGGCGUGGUAGCGGGCGCCUGUAGUCCCAGCUACUCGGGAGGCUGAGGCAGGAGAAUGGCGUGAACCCGGGAGGCGGAGCUUGCAGUGAGCCGAGAUCGCGCCACUGCACUCCAGCCUGGGCGACAGAGCGAGACUCCGUCUCAAAAAAAAAAAAAAAAAAAAAAAUACAAAAAUUAGCCGGGCGUGGUGGCCCACGCCUGUAAUCCCAGCUACUCGGGAGGCUAAGGCAGGAAAAUUGUUUGAACCCAGGAGGUGGAGGCUGCAGUGAGCUGAGAUUGUGCCACUUCACUCCAGCCUGGGUGACAAAGUGAGACUCCGUCACAACAACAACAACAAAAAGCUUCCCCAACUAAAGCCUAGAAGAGCUUCUGAGGCGCUGCUUUGUCAAAAGGAAGUCUCUAGGUUCUGAGCUCUGGCUUUGCCUUGGCUUUGCCAGGGCUCUGUGACCAGGAAGGAAGUCAGCAUGCCUCUAGAGGCAAGGAGGGGAGGAACACUGCACUCUUAAGCUUCCGCCGUCUCAACCCCUCACAGGAGCUUACUGGCAAACAUGAAAAAUCGGCUUACCAUUAAAGUUCUCAAUGCAACCAUAAA